AGGAGCCGCACCUCGGACAGCAGCAGCGGCGGCGGCCGCGGGAGGGUCCUUGUGGCGCCGGGCGGCGGGGUCCUGCGUGGAGAGUGGGACGCAACGCCGAGACCGCGAGCAGAGGCUGCGCACAGCCGGAUCCGGCACUCAGCGACCGGACCCAAGGAUCCGCCGGGGAACAAGCCACAGGAGAGCGACUCAGGAACAAGUGUGGGAGAGGAAGCGGCGGCGGCGGCGCCGGGCCCGGGGGUGGUGACAGCAGGUCUGAGGUUGCAUCAUAAAUACAAAGGACUGAAGUUAUAAAAGAGAAAAGAGAAGUUUGCUGCUAAAAUGAAUCUGAGCAAUAUGGAAUAUUUUGUGCCACACACAAAAAGCAUCUGGCACAAUGUUUUUGUUUGGUUUGGUUUGGUGUUGUAAAGAGAGAGGAUCUUGCUAUGUUUGCCAGACUGGUCUCAAACUCCUGGUCUCAAGUCAUCCUCUCACCUUGGCCUCCCAAAGCAUUAGGAUUACAGACAUGAGACAUCACACCCAGCCCCAGCACAAUGUUGAAUGUACUGAAGAUUUACCCCCCAAAAAAAAUUGUCAAUGAGAAAUAAAGCUAACUGAUAUCAAAAAGCAGAGCCUGCUCUACUGGCCAUCAUGCGUAAAGGGGUGCUGAAGGACCCAGAGAUUGCCGAUCUAUUCUACAAAGAUGAUCCUGAGGAACUUUUUAUUGGUUUGCAUGAAAUUGGACAUGGAAGUUUUGGAGCAGUUUAUUUUGCUACAAAUGCUCACACCAGUGAGGUGGUGGCAAUUAAGAAGAUGUCCUAUAGUGGGAAGCAGACCCAUGAGAAAUGGCAAGAUAUUCUUAAGGAAGUUAAAUUUUUACGACAAUUGAAGCAUCCUAAUACUAUUGAGUACAAAGGCUGUUACUUGAAAGAACACACUGCUUGGUUGGUGAUGGAAUAUUGCUUAGGCUCAGCCUCUGAUUUAUUAGAAGUUCAUAAAAAACCACUUCAGGAAGUGGAGAUCGCUGCCAUUACUCAUGGAGCCUUGCAUGGACUAGCCUACCUACAUUCUCAUGCAUUGAUUCAUAGUUCUGUCUGCCAAUGCCUAAUGUCACCAUGAGGAAGGAAACUGAAUUUUCAAGGGAAGUUUUUAUAAAAGUUAUUUUGAAGCAUUUGAACCUUAUCAUUUUCAGCUUGACAUAAAUUUCCUCAUCUUCUCUGUUUUAUCUUUUCACUGACCAUCAACUUCCAAUUCAUGGUUUCUAGUGCUCAUUACACCUCAUGCCUUUUUUAAAAAGAAUAAGGAGUACAUCCACACCUUCUCAUUCUAAAUUACCAUAAUGAAAAAUGAAUUUUUUGAAUUAUAUUUUUAAAACUUUUUGCUAUAUAAUACCUCUAUUAGCUUUAGUAGUAACCACGUGCAAUUCUUUGUAGUAAUACAAUAGAAAUGUAAUUUCCUAACCCCUAAUCCUUGUUUGUUUUGAUCUUUCAGGGUCUUCUUUUUACUGUACAGAGUUAUUUUUAAAAUAUCACCUUCUAUAUAACAUGUACCUCAAAUGCCUUAGAGUUGCAGUUACAAUUAAAGACAGAGAGAAAGGGUCACAGGCAAGAAAGAAAAGGUAUGUGUGUAGUUGAGGUUUAUUGGUAGGUGGUCAAUACGGAAUCAUUGCAGGUUUGUUUAGGCUCCAAAAAUGUCACAUAAUUUGGAAAAGCAGAAAAAGCAGUUAAAAUUGGCACCAAUUUUCUCAGCACAGGGAAUACUAUUGAUAACUGGAUUUAGCCUUUAAGAAUAUGCCUUUGUAAGUGUAGCAGCUGAAUAGGUUUUCUUGUUCGCCAUGUCUGCCUUUUUUCUCAUUUGUAUUCCCUCCCUCUGAAGAAAGCUCUACCUUUAAGUAACUAGUAUGACCUACCUGCAAGUACACCCAGGAAUCUGGGCCCCCUUACAACAUGCAGUAAUUACUAAAUCUCCUUCUGGCUAUCUGAGCAAGGGAUAUUAAAGCAGGAAAUAUUCUUCUAACAGAGCCAGGUCAGGUAAAACUAGCUGAUUUUGGAUCUGCUUCAAUGGCUUCUCCUGCCAACUCCUUCGUGGGCACACCUUACUGGAUGGCUCCAGAGGUGAUCUUAGCUAUGGAUGAAGGACAGUAUGAUGGGAAAGUUGAUAUUUGGUCACUUGGCAUCACUUGUAUUGAAUUGGCGGAACGGAAGCCGCCCCUUUUCAACAUGAAUGCAAUGAGUGCCUUAUAUCACAUUGCCCAGAAUGACUCCCCAACGUUACAGUCUAAUGAAUGGACAGACUCCUUUAGGAGAUUUGUUGAUUACUGCUUGCAGAAAAUACCUCAGGAAAGGCCAACAUCAGCAGAACUAUUAAGGCAUGACUUUGUUCGACGAGACCGGCCACUACGUGUCCUCAUUGACCUCAUACAGAGGACAAAAGAUGCAGUUCGUGAGCUAGAUAACCUACAGUACCGAAAAAUGAAAAAAAUACUUUUCCAAGAGACACGGAAUGGACCCUUGAAUGAGUCACAGGAGGAUGAGGAAGACAGUGAACAUGGAACCAGCCUGAACAGGGAAAUGGACAGCCUGGGCAGCAACCAUUCCAUUCCAAGCAUGUCCGUGAGCACAGGCAGCCAGAGCAGCAGUGUGAACAGCAUGCAGGAAGUCAUGGACGAGAGCAGUUCCGAACUUGUCAUGAUGCACGAUGACGAAAGCACAAUCAAUUCCAGCUCCUCCGUCGUGCAUAAGAAAGAUCAUGUAUUCAUAAGGGAUGAGGCGGGCCACGGCGAUCCCAGGCCUGAGCCGCGGCCUACCCAGUCAGUUCAGAGCCAGGCCCUCCACUACCGGAACAGAGAGCGCUUUGCCACGAUCAAAUCAGCAUCUUUGGUUACACGACAGAUCCAUGAGCAUGAGCAGGAGAACGAGUUGCGGGAACAGAUGUCAGGUUAUAAGCGGAUGCGGCGCCAGCACCAGAAGCAGCUGAUCGCCCUGGAGAACAAGCUGAAGGCUGAGAUGGACGAGCACCGCCUCAAGCUACAGAAGGAGGUGGAGACGCAUGCCAACAACUCGUCCAUCGAGCUGGAGAAGCUGGCCAAGAAGCAAGUGGCUAUCAUAGAAAAGGAGGCAAAGGUAGCUGCAGCAGAUGAGAAGAAGUUCCAGCAACAGAUCUUGGCCCAGCAGAAGAAAGAUUUGACAACUUUCUUAGAAAGUCAGAAGAAGCAGUAUAAGAUUUGUAAGGAAAAAAUAAAAGAGGAAAUGAAUGAGGACCAUAGCACACCCAAGAAAGAGAAGCAAGAGCGGAUCUCCAAACAUAAAGAGAACUUGCAGCACACACAGGCUGAAGAGGAAGCCCACCUUCUCACUCAACAGAGACUGUACUACGACAAAAAUUGUCGUUUCUUCAAGCGGAAAAUAAUGAUCAAGCGGCACGAGGUGGAGCAGCAGAACAUUCGGGAGGAACUAAAUAAAAAGAGGACCCAGAAGGAGAUGGAGCAUGCCAUGCUAAUCCGGCACGACGAGUCCACCCGAGAGCUAGAGUACAGGCAGCUGCACACGUUACAGAAGCUACGCAUGGAUCUGAUCCGUUUACAGCACCAGACGGAACUGGAAAACCAGCUGGAGUACAAUAAGAGGCGAGAAAGAGAACUGCACAGAAAGCAUGUCAUGGAACUUCGGCAACAGCCAAAAAACUUAAAGGCCAUGGAAAUGCAAAUUAAAAAACAGUUUCAGGACACUUGCAAAGUACAGACCAAACAGUAUAAAGCACUCAAGAAUCACCAGUUGGAAGUUACUCCAAAGAAUGAGCACAAAACAAUCUUAAAGACACUGAAAGAUGAGCAGACAAGAAAACUUGCCAUUUUGGCAGAGCAGUAUGAACAGAGUAUAAAUGAAAUGAUGGCCUCUCAAGCGUUACGGCUAGAUGAGGCUCAAGAAGCAGAAUGCCAGGCCUUGAGGCUACAGCUCCAGCAGGAAAUGGAGCUGCUCAACGCCUACCAGAGCAAAAUCAAGAUGCAAACAGAGGCACAACAUGAACGUGAGCUCCAGAAGCUAGAGCAGAGAGUGUCUCUGCGCAGAGCACACCUUGAGCAGAAGAUUGAAGAGGAGCUGGCUGCCCUUCAGAAGGAACGCAGCGAGAGAAUAAAGAACCUAUUGGAAAGGCAAGAGCGAGAGAUUGAAACUUUUGACAUGGAGAGCCUCAGAAUGGGAUUUGGGAAUUUGGUUACAUUAGAUUUUCCUAAGGAGGACUACAGAUGAGAUUAAAUUUUUUGCCAUUUACAAAAAAAAAAAAAAAAAAGAAAACAGAAAAAAAUUCAGACCCUGCAAAACCACAUUCCCCAUUUUAACGGGCGUUGCUCUCACUCUCUCUCUCUCUUACUCUUACUGACAUCGUGUCGGACUAGUGCCUGUUUAUUCUUACUCCAUCAGGGGCCCCCUUCCUCCCCCCGUGUCAACUUUCAGUGCUGGCCAAAACCUGGCCGUCUCUUCUAUUCACAGUACACGUCACAGUAUUGAUGUGAUUCAAAAUGUUUCAGUGAAAACUUUGGAGACAGUUUUAACAAAACCAAUAAACCAACAACAAAAAAAGUGGAUGUAUAUUGCUUUAAGCAAUCACUCAUUACCACCAAUCUGUGAAAGUAAAGCAAAAAAUAAUAAUAAUAAAUGCCAAGGGGGAGAGAGACACAAUAUCCGCAGCCUUACACCUUAACUAGCUGCUGCAUUAUUUUAUUUUAUUUUAUUUUUUUGGUAUUUAUUCAUCAGGAAUAAAAAAAACAAAGUUUUAUUAAAGAUUGAAAAUUUGAUACAUUUUACAGAAACUAAUUGUGAUGUACAUAUCAGUGGUGACAUAUUAUUACUUUUUUGGGGACGGGGGGUGGGUGGGGUGAAGAGAUCUUGUGAUUUUUAAGAACCUGCUGGCAAGAGUUUAACUUGUCUUCAGCAUAUUCUGAUUGUAUCAUAAUCAUUUUCUGCUGUUGCAGAGGAUGUGAAUACACUUAAGGAGCUCACAGAAUCCCAGUAGCACAAAUUGGGCUUUGGCAAAUCGUGUAUUUUGUGUAUAGAAGGAAUUUAAGGAGAGGUAUUACUUAUUUUCAUAUUGUAUUUUAACUGUUUCUCUGAUCAAAUUUUUUUACUUCCUCCUCCUGUUCCUCCCCACCUCCCUCCUUUUCCAGUUCAGUAUUUGGAGUUCAACACUGUCUCUCAAUCAGAUCAUCUUGAUCUUUUUCUUUAUCUCCCUUCCCCUUCCUAAGUCCCAUUUCUUGGUCAUAAAUAUUGCAUUAUUCACACUUUCAAACUGUGUAUUUUCUUACAAUAAAAAAUGAUGAAAAAAAAAAAGGCUUUACUUCUUUUGCAUGCACUUUAAAAACAAAACAAAACAUUUUUCAGGUUCCAAGGAAGAGCAUGAUAACUGUCAGAGCUUUUAAUUAUAUUUGUAAAUAAAAGUGUUCAUCACA